ACUCUCAGUGCUGCACUAUCCAGGAUUGCUCAUGAAGGGGAAAAUUCCUCUGCGCUUAUACAUGUGUUUCUCUGACUUUAAUUUUUCCUUGAGAUUUUGUUUUCAACCCUUUCCAAGGGGGAAAACAUUGCUUCAUGCUUUUUCUCCUCCAAGUCUAUUAAUACAAAUGGCAGGGUUUUACUGAGAAGGAGAGGAGGUAAGAUGCUCAAGUCUGGCUGGCUGCUUAGUUUAAUAACAUAGCACUUCUCUAACAGUGAGACAUCGAAUUGUAACAGUUGGUGUCUCAAGAAAGAGAAUAAUUAGGCAGUUUCAAAGCGUUGUGAUUGAACUAUUUCAGAGGCGACUAUUGACUUUAAGUGUGGAUGUAGGUCUCAGGCAACCUUCACUUUGCUUGGAACUAUUGAAAACUUUAGCACCUUGUUCAAGUUGUUAAAAGCACCCUGAAGUUUGACUAUAUCAUAGACUGACGCCUAACCUCUGCUGUGUCCUUAGGAUAUUUGAGUAUCCUAGUGUGCAGCUUAAAUUUUUCAAAAAUUUUCCUUUUGAUUCAUUUUAAUUAGAUGAGCAACAGUUUUCAUAUGCCAUAUUUUAUUGAUUUCAAGAUGCACAUUUCCCCCACAAUAGUCUUAACAAUUGAUGAUAUGAAAACAUGUCAUAGUUUAAUUGUGAGCAUUUUUCUUUCCUUAUGGUUCUUAAAAUGAAUGCUGUAUCUUACAACUGAUUGCAAGUUAGGUCCAGUAAACCAGUAACAACUUCAGGUAUGGUAAGAUCUUUCAAAAAUCAAACAGUAGAACAGUAGGGUACCACUUCACCAAAGUUAGAGAUCAUAAGCUUUAGGCUUAUGAUUAAGGCUUAUGACAAAACAACUUUGCACUUAUUAAAAAGAUACCUCUGUGUUGUCUUUGUUGUAUAUUUAGUUCAGUCCAGAAUAUUAUAAGUAGUCACGGCCAAUGAGAUUAUAAUACUCUUCAAAUCUGUAACUAUAGAAAUCUACACUUCCUGUGUCCUUGUGUUCUCACUGGGUGAGAGGAGGGGGUAGGGAUAGCAUUAGGAGAUAUACCUAAUGUUAAAUGACGAGUUAAUGGGUGCAGCACACCAACAUGGCACAUGUAUAUAUAUGUAACAAACCUGCACAUUGUGCACAUGUACCCUAAAACUUAAAGUAUAAUUAAAAAAAAAAGAAAUCUACAUUGGGGCUGAUAAUUGUAAAGGCUUUUAACAUGAGGCAGAAAUUUAGUGAUUGAAGAUUUGCAGCUUUGCUCUGGUUAUCUGCUCUGUCACCUUUAAACCUUCAUUUCACUUGUAAAACAGAACACUAACAUUUUUUACUUCUUGCGUGACUGUCAUAUCAUGGGUGCAUUAACAGCUCUGAAACGUUUUUGUUUCUGAGAGGAAAGAUGGUGUGUAAAUAAACAUUGGAAUUAUGACUUUUUCUAUGUAGACUUUCCUGUGAAGCUUAAAAUAAGGAAAGGAAUAUUAGGGAUCUUUCUUUCUAGUGAUAAAUAUAAACAAAGCCAUUCUGUCAUCUCCCUUCUGCAGGAUGACACCAGUGGAAUCUUUCAACUCUCAAGGCUGAUAUUGAUGUAGUCCUCCACUAAAUGAAUUAUUUGGUACUAGAUGGUUACAGUUUUUGCAGUAAUUUAUUAGGAAUAAAAACCACCUGCUAAUUCACUUCAAUCUUUUAUGUCUUGGGCAUUUGAUGUGCCUAUACCUUUGCUUACCCCUUAAGUUCACAGUGUUCAUGAAGGUGGUGCAGUGUUUUCGUUUUUCCUGUCCUCACUUUCUUUACAGUAGCAGUCAUCUGCUCUUCAUAGAAACUCAGUUCUGACACACAGCAUGGACAGAGGAAACUGCAGUUUACUUAACGUAAACCUAGGUCUGCAGUUUCCUCUUCUUGUUAUAACAAUAAUGACCAAACCCUGAAGUUACAUACAGAUUUCCUUUCUUUUAUGAUUUUAAAAUGCUUCAUCGACUUCAUCCACCAUUCCUGGGCCAAAGCUAGUUAAGUCGACAGUGAUAAAAUUUGAGUUAGAAUCCAAGUUGCCUAUUGAGUCAUUCUUUUGACUAACCUUCAUUACUUUCCAGUUCUAGAAUGCCACAUAGAUGCCAAAGAGAGAGCUAAUUUGUAGCACUACUGCACAGGCAAAGACAUAAAUUUGAUAGAAUAAAGCCUUUGUUGCUGGUACAUCUUGUUACAAAUUGAAGGGGAUUACAGCUUUCUCAGUAGGCAUUUCUAAUAUUUUCUUAACUGCUAAAUGCUGUGAUUAUAAAUGCAUGCCAUUAGAGAAAUGCUUCACUCUAUGCUUUUGCCAAGGUGUUUCUGAAAUUUAAGAAGUUAAAUGUAUAAUUAUCGCAAGCUUCUCAGGAAGCACUCCAUUUUUCUAUUUUCUAUUAACUAGCUGUAGGCACAAUGAGCAAGCACUCAUUCCUAUGUGUUGAAAAUUAUUAUGGGAGGACUUUCAGAAGGGGAAAGAAAUGGGCUGUGUCUUCUAAACAUUAUGAUAGUAGAGUUAACAUUGAGUUGUUGGUUCUUUAAAGAAAUUAUCUCUGAUGUAGGCAUUGUAUUUCCUAGCCUUAAUUCUGUGACUGUGCCAACAGAGCAAGGGACGUGUGUUAUCAGAUGGGGACCUUUGAGCUUGACCCUGAAGAAUGACUAAUGGUCAUAGAAGAAGGCAGGGGACAGCAUUUCAGGCAGAGGGACCCAUGGGAAGAUACAUGACUGCAGUCCUGGUGAUUCCUAGGGAAUGGAGAGGGGUGGGCUGGGAGUCAGCCUAAAAUUCCAUUAUGAAAGACUGGUAAGCUAAAAAAGUCUACCAGCUACCCUAAGGAGCUUAAACUUGCCUUUUGGUCAAAGGAAAGCCAUCAAAGAAGGGAAGUGGCAUAAUCAGAUGUGGCCUUUGUAAGAUCUCUCUGGCAUUGCUUUAGAGGAAGAAUUGAGUGAAGAAGAGGGAAAUGUUGGAAAGAACCUUUAGAAAGCUACCAUAGUGAGUCAAGUGAGAGGUGCCAGCCUGAACUGGGGCAAUGACCAUAAGAACUGAGGAGGGAGUAAAUGUGGAAAGUCAUUUACACAGUAAAAUUGACAGAAUUCAGUGACUAGCAAUGGGGGAUGUGCAUGCUAUUUUAUAUUAAGCAAUUUGUAAGGAUUCUUUGGUAUAGUGGCAGACAUAAGAAUGUUGUGUUUCUUACCACCUUUGCCAAAAAGCUAUGUAAGCCAUUUCCCUUGCUUUGUUUGCCUGCAGUUUGCUUCAGGUAGCUGAGAUGUUAGUAUUUAUCUCACUGACAGAUUGUUAGGUGGGGUUCUGGCAAACACUAUGGGGACUACACAAACUUUUCUUUCCAGAACCCUUUGAAAAUACCUUAAACAGAGAGAAUCUCUGGUAGCUCCCAAAUAAACCGACAUAUUUGGCCAGAGCUUUGGCAUUUGCUGCAAUAUGUGUGCCUUCCUCAGAAUUAACUGGGAUUUUAGGGUGGCUCUCCUGAUCUCUGUAAUCUGAGUUGGUGUUACUAUACUUCUAUUCUAGAAUACUCUCUGUCAUCCAUUCAUUUGCUAACUUUUGUUCAAGCCGAUGUCAUAGAGGAGCCAGGCUAACUAUGGUGGCUCCCAACUAUGUGGCUCCUGCCCUCAAGAAGUAUAGUCUAGUUGUGGAGGAAAGAUAUCAACACAACUAACUGAGAUACAAGGAAGCAGUGAAGAGAAUCCCAAGAGAGACACAUAGGAGUUUGAAGAAGAAUUUACACCUGAGAAAGCAGGAUUCUUUCAUAGGGCAGAAGUAGUUUGACCUGGACCUUAAAUUAGGUUUUGGGUUGGAUUUAAAGAAUCCACAUUGAAGAAGAGUAUUCCUAGUGGGAAGAAUAGCAUUAGAAAAUGCACAGAGAUACCAAAAUAUUAGAUGUUUUUUGGAACUCUGAAACGAUUUCAUGUUUCCAGAAUACCAAGAAUUGGGGGUGUGGGAGGGGAGGCAGGAGAAGGAAGAUUUCAUGAGAAAUGAGAUUGGGACCAGACUGUGGAGGAUUUUGAGGGCUGAGAAGUUUUACUUCAUUCUAGAAAUAAUGAGGAACGACUCAGCAUUUGUUUGCCUGCAGUUUGCUUCAGGUAGCUGAGAUGUUAGUAUUUAUCUCACUGACAGAUUGUUAGGUGGGGUUCUAACUUUUCCUAAGGAAGAUGGUUGAGGCAGGGCCUUCAUGAGAUAAAUUAUAUUAUUUCAAUCUGACUGAACAGUGACUGAAUAGUGAGGGAGCUGAAGAGUGAUUAAGCAGACUUGGGGCCAGAGUGAAUUCAAGUCUGAUUGCCUCUGGAGGGUGUCUUCCUUCAGCCUUCAUCACUGGAGUGAGGACUGAUAGGUGGCCCAGAAGCCAAGGUAACCGGAACCACAGCAGUCCUUCGAAAGAGGGCAUGCACUCAGAGGGCAGCUCUGGAGGACAGAGACAGAAAGAAUACGUAGGGAGGGAUGGGGGUUGGGGGGCGGGAAUGCAGAAAAAGAAAAGGUGCUUGCCCAGUCGUAACUUAGAUUUGAAAAGCUUAUAAACUUUUCAUAUUUUAUUUUCAGUAAAAUAGUUACAUCAAAGUAUAUGACUAGAUGGAUGUGGGUCCUAUUUCCAGGAAUAUAGCUGCACUAUUCACCAGAAAACUGAACCUGUAUUUUCCCGAAAUGUAGUUUAUGCUUUGUAGUGUAUUAAAUUGUAGAUUAGAAAUACCAACAAUAGCUCCUAACCUGACUUCCUGACUUCCAACUGUAGAAAUGAGCAGUAUCUGUAAAAUGUAUGUGAAAACUUGGUUCAGCAAUACUUUCCCUAGGGAUCCUGUCUGUAUCCCUCCCUUGCCCCACCCCAUUUUCUUCUGUUCCUUUGUUAAGUCUGGGGACCCACCCUACUUCCUUCCCCUUUUCUAAUUCACUCAUGAAAUAUGGAUGGGUGGGAAGGGGAUUUUGCACACUCUGAAACUGCAUCUUGGCACAGUCUGCUGCCAGGGUAGGGUCUCUAUCACUCAGCCUCAACCGGAAUUUCCUUUUCCCUGUUUCCUGCAGCCUCAUCCUGGAAUUCUGCCUACGUCAAAGGUUCCUUGUUUAAGGAUUACGAGGGGAGAAGUGGUUUGGAGUAUUCUGGCUACUGUCACACUUAUUUACAUAUUAAAAGUUGGUCUCUACCUUUUCCCAAAUUUCAUUUUGUCUCUUUUUAAGCAGUUAAAUAUAAGGUGAAAAUCCUCUUUUUACUCUAUAUGAAAUACUAAAAGGAAAAGAGGUUUGAUCAUUGUUUUCAAACUUAUAAUUGUACAUCUAGGUGAGUAGUUUCAAGCAAUCCCAGCAUUAUUUGAAGUUUAUCAGUAAUUUAGUUUAACCAAGAAACUACUUACUAAAGAGAAGUAGAACUUUCUAACAUUACUGUAAUAGAAUUGAAAGUCACAACUAGGGUAUAAUAGGCAAUUCAUAAUACAUUAAGUUGCCCAAUUAUAAACUGAGAAAUCACCUCAUUGAAACCAGGUUAUUUUUCUUAAUAACAAAAUCCUGACUUUGUGUUGGAUUGGUAUUAAAGUAUCUUUCCAUUGGAAUUAGGCUUCCUGGAGUGAGUUAUUAUAGUCCAUUUUUAAUAGGGAAUAAUAUGGCCACAGAGUAACAAAAAAGUAGAAGUAGCUAGUUCUUGCCUCCAAGAAGUUUACAGUCUAGCUGGGGAAAGAAUUUAUACAUGGAAAACAGUUAACCAUUCAAGACAGCAUUUAAUGAAGUCUCUAAAUAAGACAUUUAGAGGGAAGUAAAAUCUGGCAAACACAUUUCACAACUGCAGCAAACCAUGCUCUUCUCAUUUAUUUAGGAACAAGGUUUACAAGUUUGGUUCACUGUGUGUGCUCUUUAAAUUCUAGCUUUUCCUCCAGAAAAAUAGCAGUUAACUGCCAGUGAAAGUCAGUGGUGUGCUCCUGCUGUCUGGUGGAACCAUCUGCUCAUUAGCUGUAUUUUUAGGUUUUCACAAGAAGCCCACUGCAAGUCCUAACAUUUUUAAAAAAUUAGUUUGAGCGGUUUUGAAGAGAGAGGAAUUUGUCAUUAUGCUAUUUUUUGACGGUGCUCAAGUUUAUUUUAAAAGGCUCAAUCAAGAACAUUGAUACUGGCUCAGUUUGUUUGAUUUAUCAAACUCAUGUUAUCAAAGGGUCCUUUUAUUCUCUGCUGUACAAAUGCUGCUCCUAGCUUUAUUAGGUUCUUAUUCUUGUAAAAUUAAAAUAGCCAUAUCAUCUGCAAUAUGGUUGAAAAAUCAUUAAAGUGAAGUAUUGAAAAGCAGGUUAUUUGCCACUGUUGUUUUGCCAUCACCCUCCUCCCCCAGUGGUAUAUCUCACUCCAGACCCCAGGUGACCUUAUAUUCUUUUCUUCUCUACCCCCAUCAAGGCCUGAUCUGCAUUAAUGUAACAGUGUUACUACCAUGUAGUCUGGUGUCUGAUCAGGCAACACUAGAAACUUUUGUCAGGCUGGUGUUAUUUGGGUUUAUAAUGAAUGUUUUAAGACAAAAAGUUUAGGGAAAGGAUGCACAGACAGAUGGAGAGUUGUUCAUGAUAACUGUGUACUUCCAAGGUUUGGAAAAAUAAAAAGAAGAGAUAUCAAGAAGUAAAGAGACAUAGGCAGCAAUUUACAGUGUGGCUUGGUUCCUGAAGGACUGCCCUGAUACAUCUCUGACCUCAUGAACUGAUGUUCUGCGAGAAACUCAGAGACUGAAUUCAGUUUACCUGUGUGGUCAGCAUCCAAGUGCUGUGGAAGCAUUUAACAGGGACCUUGGCUAGUCUAGGGAGUCAUGCACAUUUCCCUGAGAGAGAGAGAGAGACAGAAUCUGAAGGGUCAGGAGAGCUAUGAAAAGUGAGGAGGGAUGGGUGUUCCAGGCAGAGGAAAGAACACAUGUGAGGCCGGGUGUGGUGGCUCACGCCUGUAAUCCCAGCACUUUGGGAGGCCAAGGCGGGUGGAUUACGAGGUCAAGAGAUUAAGACCAUCCUGGCUAACACGGUGAAACUCUGUCUGUACUAAAAAUACAAAAAAUUAGCCAGGCAUGCUGGCGGGUGCCUAUAGUCCCAGCUACUCGGGAGGCUGAGGCAGGAGAAUGGAGAAUGGCGUGAAUCCGGGAGGCGGUGCUUGUGGUGAGCCGAGAUUGUGCCACUGCAUUCCAGCCUGGGCAACAGUGCGAGACUCGGUCUAAAAAAAAAAAAAAAAAAAAAAGAGAACACAUGUGAUAACACAAGGGGCCUGAUGUGGAGAAGAGAGCAGCUUUAGAAACAGAACCAACCAGCUGGAGCCUAAGUGUGGACUGUGGAUGGGAGAGGUAGGGCCAGGUGAAGAAGGUGCAGGAGCUGGAGGAUGCAGGACCUGUGGGUUUAUCCAAACAUUGUGUGCUAAGAGCAAUAGGAAGCUUUUGUGUAGAAUUUAAGCAAGAAGGAAGGAAAAAUGAUUAGAUUUAAAUUUUUAACAUUCCUCCGUUGCAAUGUGGGAACAGAUUUGAAGGAGGAGAAUGGGUCACACUCACUCCUUCAAAGCUUCCUGGUCCCACUUCCCUCACAGUCCUCUCUGUCGAUUUCACAUUAAGUAGUAACCAGCAUACAUGCAAAAGGAUUUGCUGUGGGCAGCUCAAGUCAGGGGACUUCAGUUCCAGGAAGACAGAAUGUCCAGUGAUAGUUCACUUCUAAUUUAUUACCUUUUCCCUAAAAUAUACUGCUAUAUCACCAUUUUUCUUUAACAAGUUGGCUUGGAGUCAGUCCUGUUUUUGUAGAAAUGAAUUUUGUGCAUGCAUAUAAUGUGAAUAUCUUUUGUUAAUAAACACCAUGCAGGCAGAUAUGUUCGCUUUAAAUACAACUUACUGUGCUGUAUAUUUGCCUCAUAUUGAUUCAGCCAAAGUUUGGUGAUUUCUGAGUCAUUCAUAUACUUUGGUUGCUAAAGAUGAGGAAAAGAAAUUUAUAAAAGAUGUCCAUGUAGGAUGCAAAGAACCUUUUUUUCCUUUUGCAGUGGGAAGUGGGUGGAAAGGAAAAAUUCCAUCUGGCAUCCAGCAGUCCUAAAUGUUGUUUUAAGAUAGCAAAAAUAGAAGAUUGCUGAAAAUAUCAUAACAGAACAUAACAGACUGUGGGCAAGUGUACAGUACAUUUUUUCUAAUAAAUCAUGCUAAAUAUGCGUAUUUUACUUAUAACAUGACCAAGUUCUUGUUUGCUGUUACAUAAAAAUUUGUCUUUAUUUUUUGUAUUAAAAUUAUCUGCUCUCUUUUUGAAGCAAAAAGGAUGAUUGUUUUGGUCUGAAGAGAUCAGUGUUGCAGUACUUAGGUUUAACUGGAAUAGGUUUUUGAAUUUUGCAGUUUUCCCCUCUUUUUCCAGCAUUUCCCUCCUACAUUUAAAAAAAAAUGGAGAAAUAAGAUGUGGCAUGUAUGUUCAUUUAUGGCACAUUUGUACAUAAGUCAGUGAACAAGGCUCAACCAUUUUAACAAAUCCUUGUAAAUGUCCUCUUUGUUCAGGUUCCAGGAAUGACUGGGCACGACUGAGGCAAAGUGAGUCAGAGUAAAGGAUUAGGGGCACCUCAAGAUCCAAGAAACACAUAAUAGUAGAGAAUAAUGGUGAUAAUGAGACAAUUAAGAUGUCAGAAAGUGGCUUGGAGGUAUGGAUUCACAAGAAGGCUCAAAAAACUUAAUGAGUCAUAAAGCAUAUCUGGGUGACCUCAGAGGUGCGAGUCGGGGUGGAAUGUGUCAAGGUAAAAUUUUUGCCCUCCACCAUCAAAGAGAGGAGACAGUGGUACUUCCUACAGAUAGUUCUUAAAACCUUUCAUGAUCUUGCCUUGGCUAGGAUUUAGAGAAGUAGAACAAGCUUUAUGUUGACACCCCUGUGAAUAAAGAAUUCUAACAUUCCCCAAAUGGCACAAUGCAUAAUAAAAUCCCAAAGUGAGUUUUAUGAUUGCUGGAUGCUAUCACUUUCUCCCUGCUCAGUCAACUUAUUGUUAUUACAAAUUGGGGGUUUGUGAUGAUGCAUUAUUUUUCACCAUCAGUCUGAGUAGUCUGGAGUUUUCCUCUGAGAGUCAUAGGCAUUAGAAAGAACUUUAGAUAUCAUGUGUCUUGAUGGCUUGGGGAAGGAAAACUUUAUUUCUAAAACUGGCACCUGCUAAAUAGGAUUAUAAGCAGUUUCCUCUAAAAAGGGGAAAAUAUAUUCUAAGACCAUUAGUUCUUUUGGAAGUGCAUUAGUCACAAGAAAAUGUUAAAACAUUUCCAUUGAUAAUAUCUUCUAGCAAAAGUAAAUACCUUUUAGCCUCUGUAAUCAGAAGCAAUUUUGUUAAUAGUUUGUUAACAAAAAGUGUAAUUCUUUAGUUUGUUAGAGAACUUCUUAAUUCAGGCUUUGUGCUUUUAUCUCUUUGUGUUCCUGAAGUUAGAUUUUGUGAGGCCCUAAAGUGAGGCUGGGCUGAUCGACGUGACCCUUGCCCUAAGACAACACUUCUUUAGAACUACUCCUCCCCUACCUAUUAGCAGUUAGCCCCUCAAAAAUUAGUGACUCAUGAAAGUGGGCACAAACAAUUUGGCCAGCAAAAAAUAAAUGGGAUCAUUCAGUUCUUCUCAUUAAACACCCAUCUGGAAGCACAUGUCUAAAAAUUAUCUCAGUAUUAAAACAACACUCAGGUAUAACUCUAAAAAUGGUGGGGGGGAAGGAUAGUUGAAGCUACAGACAUAAUACUUUCCUCUCUAAUAAUAUGUAUGAGUAGAAUUUUAGAAGAUAUGUAAGUAAAAACUGUAGGAUACGAAAUGGAGAGAUGAGAGCACACACGGCCCAAGUAGGUAUUGAUUUACACCUACAGGUUUGUGAUUAAAGGAUGAGCCAAGAAAGGGAUAAAAGGAAGAUCUUGAGCCUGCACAAGGCAGACUUCUGCCUAUUCCUUAAAAUCUGAGAAAAGAAACUUUGGAACAAAAGAGAGAGCCAAUUUUAUUCUGAUUGUCUUUCAGGAAUAUACUUGAAUGCCAGAUGUUUGUGCACAGAAGCCUUUCAUGACUUGUUGAACUAUUAAAUGCCAUUGCCAUUAUAAUUUGGCAAUCACCUCUGACCUUUAUCUCAAUUGUCAGUAGAUCCCAUUUCCAUCCCAAGUCAGUAAAUCUAAGUUCCUCUCCUUUAGUAUUACUCAUAAUCUUGGCACAUAGAGGAGAUGUGCACAGACCUGACAAAAUUCACCACACCCUGGAAAGAACCUUAUUAAUAAUGAUCAGAGUGGCUGUAGGUACCUUCAGCAUCUGCAGCUGCACCAAUAAUGGUGCCCCACACUUUGUGGUUUGUGAUUUUUGCAUCUUAGCUCUGACUUCUACUUUACGUUCCAUAUCUGGCUAGUCCAGUUCUUCCCUAGAAUCUUUGGAGAAGAACGUAGCAAAAGAGUGUCUUGCUGGUCUCAUUUUGGUCCAAACCCAAGUUUUUAGAUUGCUUCAAUCCAGACUAGAGAAGCAAAAAAUGGUGACUUUUCCUUCUGAGUGAUUGAUGAUAGUAGGCUGCAGACAUCUCAGUCUAGGGAACCCUAUAAAGAAGGAAGAAUUGGGCAGCACAGGCCUGUGGAAGACCCAGUGAAGGGAAUUAUUCCUUAGCUGAGUGUGAUGAGCCAGAGACACAGGGAUUUUGGUCACACUGGUUAUUGCACUGGUCUUCAGACAGAGGCCAGCAUCCCUUAUGAUCAUCCCUAAUGAUCUGUGCUGAGCUGAUCAGACAGUUUCUCCACCAUCAGCAGCUUAAUUCAGAUUCCUUCAUUUGAACUCACAGAGAUGAUUAGAAAGAGUUAUACUAGUGAAGAUAGAAGACAACCAAAUAGCUAUUUAGCUUGUUGCCACCAGUGUAGUCAUUCAGUGACAAUACAUAAAGUUAACUUUGUUGAUGGCCUAAAUAAUUUUAAUGUCAGUACAACCUUUUUUUUAUAAGUAGAGCAAAAUUUUAAAAUAUCUGGCUAAGAUUAAUUUAUUCUUACCUUCAUUCACUGAGAAAAGCAUUUGUUGAGCACCUAUGAACAAGACAUCACAUGAAAUAGAACAGAGACAGAAAUGAGCAAGGUGUGAUGUGAGCCCCAAAGAUACCGGCAUUUAAUGAGACAGAAGCAUGUGAAAUGAGACAGAAGCAUGUGAAAACCCAGACAGGAAAACCCAGUAAAGAAGAAGGGCAAAAACACACAGAAGAGAGGGCCAGGAAAGGCUUCCAGAUGGGAGGAAAGAGUGCACUUUGAAUAAGGUAUUUGUUUCCAGAAAAUUGUUUUCUCACAUUCCUGUAAGGCAUUUGCUAAAUUAAGCAUCAUCUUUUUUACUUCCUGGGUUAUGGCCAGGUCAGGACACAAAUCAUAAAUGACAAAGAUUAUAAAUCUCAAAUCUAAAGGAGGUUGCAUAUUGGAGUUUACAAUUCAUUCCCUUCCCCAUUUUCUAGCUACAAAAUAUACUUGUCAAAAAAAAUUUAGUAUAUUAUACAUAGUCCUUGGCGUGUUUCACUGAUUGAAUUUGUUUUUGAAAACAGGCUUCAUCUGGAAGAGGUUUACAGGUGUUUAACAGUCCAGAGUAAAGUAGCAAGCAACUUGCUGGAAUUUAUAGCACAUUUCUGUUAAAGAAUUUUUGUUGUUUAAAGUUGUUCUACUACUGUAAAAGUAAUGUAUGCCCUUCAUAGAGAAUUUAGAAAUAAUAGAAAGUUACAAGGAAGAAAAUAAAAAUUUAAUGAUAAACCACUAUUUCCUCCCCCCACCCCCUGGCUGUCCCCAGUCUUUGUAUUCUGAGGCUUUCCUCAUAUUUUCAUGACAUGCUUUACUUAGCUACCCUUCCCUGGGGGAAUUUUGCUAUUAUAAACUAUAACGCGCAACUCUCCAAAAAUCUUUAACUAAGUUUAUAUUCUUAAGGAUAAAUUCCUAGUAGCAGAAUUACUACUUAUAAAUAUAAACUGCAUUACUAUCUUUUAUGUUUUUACCCAACCACUUUCCAAAAAGCUUGUGCUAGUUUUUACUUAAAUCAGCAAUAUAUGAAAUUACUUGUUUUGUAAUCCCUUCAUCCUAGCUUUCACCUUCAUUGAGUGUUACAAUUUUGAGUAGGAGAAACUAUGUUAUCUUUGUCAGGUUGAUGGUGGCCAAGGGAGAGGGAGGAAAAUACUAUCUUGUUCAAAUGUACAUCUCUAGUGUAGUUGAAUAUUUGCGACUUAUAUCAACCUAUUUCUCUUUCUUCUGUAAGUAAUUUAUUUUUCUCCUUUCUCAUUUUUCUCACUGAAAUUUUCUUAUUGAUUUGGACAAGUUAUUUACAUAUGAAGGAUAUAAAAUUUUGUCAUAUUUGUUGCAUAUUGUUUUCCUCAGUUUGUUUUCUACUUAGUUUGUUUCCUAAUUAAUUAUUUUUAUACACAUGAGUGGAAAUGUUUUUUAUUUUUAAUAUUGUCUUUAAAAUGAGAAAUCCCUUCCUCAUUAAGUAAAAUUUUAUUUUAUUUUUUCUAUUCCUUUUGGAGUUGCACUUUUCACUCAGACCUCUUUUUUUUUUUUUUUUCUUGUGACAUGGGUCUCACUCUGUUGCCCAGGCUGGAGUGUGAUGGAAAAAUCACAACUCACUGCAGCCACAAUCCUCCCACCUCAGCCUCCAGAGUAGCUGAGACUACAGGCAUGUACUACCACGCCCAGCUAAUUUUUUGGUAUUUUUGUAGAGACAAGGCCUCACUAUGUUGCCCAGGCUGGUCUCCAACUCCUUAGCUCUGGAAAUCCUCCCAACUCACCCUCCUAAAGUGCUGGGACUAUAAGCAUUAGCCACUGAGAUUGGCCUCACUUGGAUUUUUUAAUAUAGCUGUGAUUUAUUUUUGUAAUGUAAGAUUUCUUGAUCAACUAUCACAUGCAUAAUUUUUCUUCAGUUAAUUUACUAUUUUAUUACUAGCAUCAAAGACAUUCAUUUUAUUCUGGAAGAAUUGAAAUUCUGUGAUGAACAAACUACCUCCCAAGUUAAUAUGUUGAGUGCUGAUUUAGUAAAUCACUUUACCUCUCUGAGCUUCAGUCUUCUCAUCUAAUAAAUUAAGAUAUUAGAUGUCUAAGAUUUCUUCUAGCUCUAAAAUUCCUUUCUUAACUUGAAGACACCCUUCCCCCCAGAUUCUGCAAUAUCCAUGCUUUUGAGUGUUGAACUCUUUCUGGGAAAAUGUCACCAUUUUAUAAAGGAUACCAAUUGAUUACUCAGGAAGUUCUGAGUAGCUCUUUUUUCACUCUGAUUGAAUAUGUCUAUCAAUGCCAAGAAUCAUUCUGUUCUUUUAUGUUCUAAAAAUACUCCAGUGGAUAGAACUUCUAAAAAUUUACUCUGUGAAAUGGUGUUGAUACAGGACAGAUGGCUGAUCUAGCAUAUCCAGCUAGAAGUGUCUGUUAUCAGGACAUUAAAAUGAUAUUUCAAGUCAAGUCAUUAAAUAUUUGGAAUUGUUUCUCUGAGAUCAGAAUGUCCUGAGGAGGAUCAAAAUCUGGAAUUCCCAAAUCUCUGCAGUGAAGGAAAUGCUAGCUCUUACUGCCUUGAACUCUUAGAAAUACCAAGAAAGUAACCUAGUUCUUGAUGUUGGCUAGGUUCAUUAGCUGCUACCCACAGCCUAGCUCCAAAUUACUGUUUUUAAAACAUGCAGAUUUUUGUCUCUUACAUGUCUAUCUGUCACGUGAAGAAUUUACUCUUUGAGAGCAUGCCUAUAUUUUAUUUGAACUUUUAUCCCCAGUGUUUAGCACUAGGCUUUCAGUCAGUGUUUGUGGAACUGGAGCUGAUAGAGAAGGAAAUUGUGGGUGGUUUGAGAUGUUUCCCACAGUCGAGUACUUCAAAUCACAUCUGUAAAAAUCCAAAGUUUUACCAGCUUCAGGAUUCCAGUUCAUUGGAUAUUUAAAGUUUUAAAUAAGAAGUUUUCUACCUUAGAGAAUUAACCUGGAAAUGAUAAGCAGAAAAGGCAGGAAGGUUCAUCACCGGUAGUCACUUUGUAAUACAGAAAAGUCUUUGGAAGAAUCCAUCCCUGGUAAAGAGUGGAUGCAGACGUUCAGACUUUAAUGGAUCACAGGUUGUGGAGCAAAGAUCUUACCUGGGCAGGUUUGUACGUGAGGAUUUUGACCUUCUUUGGCCCUCCAGGUGCACAUUAAUAUUCAGGAAAAGAGAAUUUGUUUUUCAUAUGUGUUAUCACUUUAAUAUUAAUUCCUCACUUAAAUACUAAUUCCUUUUUUGUUCCCCCAGUCUGUCCUCCUCUUCUCUCCACACCUAUUCCCUCCCUUGGAAAAAAAGGCAGGAGAGAUCUACCCCUAUGCAAGCAAAUUCAUCUUUGUCUUAUUUUAACCUUCGCUCUUCCUUUUUACCUUCUGGUUUUUUGUUUACUUUUUUGCUUGCCUCUCAAAUCAUUUUAGCAAUAUUUCAUUACAUCUUACAUUCUCUUAACCUAUUUUUAAUACCAACUUCCUGUUACUGUUCCAUGCACCAAGAGUGCCACUUUGUCUACCUUUAUCCCAACCUUGUUUCAAACUGUGAAAUGAAGUUUCUGAGAUGGCUACAGCAGAGACCAAAGGCGUGCCUCCCUAAAAACACCAAGGAAUGUACAAAACAUGAAAAAACAGGAGUGUUUACUUAAGAUGCUUUGUAUCUCCUCACUCUCAUUCCAUGUGAUCUGGCAGCUGCUACAGUAGCUAGAAAUUUUUCAUUCCAUAACUUGCAUAAAUACUGAAACUCCCCCUUUGGAUUGCUACUUUGCCCUCAUGGAAGUUCCACAGGCAUGCGUGCACACACACACAAGCAUUUCCUCACGUACACACAUGCAGAUGCUCAUUGACACACACGCACAGGAAAUUUGGGAAGAGUGAUAGAGUUCUUUGACUUGAAGCCUUUCAAUUUUUUAGAGUUUAUUUCCUUUUUAAGUUUGAAGAAUACUUCUGCUGGGUCUGCUCAGACAUAAGAACUAGCUUUUUCAAAUAAUUUCAGUUUAUGAAUUAGUUCUUCACUGAGUCAGGAGGUAUCAAACACAACUAAGUUUCAGAUCCUAUGGGAGGAAUUUGAGAGGAGAAGUCAAAGCCAUAGGAACCAGUCAGGGCUAGCUAUUUUAUGCUGCUCUGAAAAGUCAUGUUAUCCUCUUGUUGUUCAGUUGUAAAGGCUUCUGUAAAACUGCUGCCAUGGAUUAUUCAAACCCCACGGGACAAAUAUAUCUGCAACCAGAAUGUAGAAACUUUAAUCAUAAUUUAGUGUAGGUUUCUGUCCUACCUUUGGGCUGCUAGUGAAAAGCAGUGAUUCGGGUUACUGGCAAUUUUUUUCCCUUUCUUCUUCUACAUUUCAGGAAAUGCUUAAGGAUCUAAUUUAGAUUUCUGCAUCCUCAUUUCUUCCGACGUGAUCUCAAAUAGGCCUCUGUCAGGUCAUGUGUGCACACUGUACCAUGCCUCAGUUGCCCGUUGACCCAGGCUGCUUGGUUUCAGGGAACUGAGGCACUGCUGAGGAGCCCUGGUCCACAGCAUGCAGGUGCAAGAUGAUGAAGUGACGACUGUUCAGGUUAAAGAGCAAGACCAGAGCGUCCUGGUGCUGAAGAAAGUGCAGUGCUGUGGCCCAGCCCCCACAGCUGGGAGUGCGGAGAGCCAUUGGAGAUAUGUGGUGGUGUCCGGGACCCCGGAGAAGAUUUUGGAGCACCUUUUGAAUGACUUGCACCUGGAAGAAGUCCAGGACAAAGAAACAGAGACCCUCCUGGAUGACUUCCUUCUCACGUACACUGUCUUCAUGACAACUGAUGACUUGUGCCAGGCUCUGUUAAGGCACUAUUCUGCUAAGAAGUAUCAAGGCAAAGAGGAAAACUCAGACGUUCCGCGUAGGAAACGUAAAGUCUUGCAUCUUGUUUCCCAGUGGAUUGCUCUGUACAAAGACUGGUUACCUGAAGAUGAACAUUCAAAAAUGUUUUUAAAGACCAUAUAUAGGAAUGUACUGGAUGAUGUUUAUGAAUAUCCAAUACUUGAAAAAGAAUUGAAAGAAUUUCAAAAGAUACUUGGAAUGCACCGUCGUCACACUGUAGAUGAAUAUUCACCACAAAAAAAGAAUAAAGCCCUUUUCCACCAAUUCAGUCUUAAGGAGAACUGGCUCCAGCAUAGAGGAACUGUGACUGAAACGGAGGAAAUUUUCUGCCACGUGUAUAUAACAGAGCACUCCUAUGUCAGUGUGAAGGCAAAAGUUUCCAGUAUAGCCCAAGAGAUCCUAAAAGUCGUGGCAGAAAAGAUCCAGUAUGCAGAAGAGGAUCUGGCUCUGGUGGCCAUCACAUUCUCUGGGGAAAAGCAUGAACUUCAGCCAAAUGACUUAGUCAUCUCCAAAUCCCUCGAGGCAUCUGGUCGAAUAUAUGUCUACCGGAAAGACCUGGCGGACACUUUGAACCCAUUUGCAGAAAAUGAGGAAUCACAGCAAAGGUCGAUGAGGAUUUUGGGAAUGAACACUUGGGAUCUUGCUCUGGAAUUAAUGAAUUUUGAUUGGAGUCUAUUCAAUUCAAUUCACGAGCAAGAGCUGAUCUACUUCACGUUCAGCAGACAGGGAAGUGGGGAACACACUGCAAAUCUCAGCCUUCUGCUCCAGAGAUGCAAUGAGGUCCAGCUUUGGGUGGCCACGGAGAUUCUGCUCUGCAGCCAGCUGGGCAAGCGAGUGCAGCUGGUGAAAAAAUUCAUCAAAAUUGCGGCUCACUGCAAAGCCCAGAGAAACCUGAAUUCUUUCUUUGCCAUUGUGAUGGGUCUCAACACUGCUUCUGUCAGUCGACUGUCGCAGACCUGGGAGAAAAUCCCUGGGAAGUUUAAGAAACUUUUCUCUGAACUUGAAAGUUUAACAGAUCCUUCCCUAAAUCACAAAGCCUACAGAGAUGCAUUCAAAAAGAUGAAGCCACCAAAAAUCCCUUUCAUGCCCUUAUUGCUUAAAGAUGUAACAUUUAUUCAUGAAGGAAAUAAAACUUUUUUGGAUAAUCUUGUCAAUUUUGAAAAGCUGCAUAUGAUCGCAGACACUGUCCGAACCCUGAGACACUGCAGGACUAACCAGUUUGGUGACCUGUCUCCAAAAGAGCAUCAAGAGUUAAAGUCCUAUGUUAAUCACCUGUAUGUCAUUGACAGCCAGCAGGCUCUGUUUGAGCUCUCACACAGGAUCGAGCCUCGGGUGUGAGCCCCACUGCCUCACCUCCCCUGUAUCUGCAGCACUUUGAGCUACGGGAAUGUCUAUGCCAAGCACGUUGCUUUCCUGUGAGAAAAGAAGUUGCUGAGUUUUAUCAGUAUAACCCAAGACAUUCACAGGAAAGCCAGCCAAAGCGUGUUCAGGAAGUGAUGUCAGCCACCAGAGAGGGGGAGAGGUUUCUCCAUGCUACUCUCGGGACAAGAAGGCAGAAGGAGAGUCAGAAGCAUUCUUGAGAUGGAGAAGGCUGGUUUCUUAUGAUCACAUUGUUGAUCCAGUCCAGUUUUCAAUAUGAGAUGUGCCAGCAUCAAGACAAGACAACGUCUUGACAUGCAAUGACCAAAUAUUUCAUUAAGAGCGUGCAUGAAACAGGAAGGAGUUUUUACUUUGCCUAGUUUUAGAUUACUGUCCAUAAGCUGUCAAAGAAGUCAUUCUUUUGAACACCUGAUGACAGAGACAGCAUCUCUAGAUCUCCAGGGAGGAGAGGUUUCUGUUGAUACAACCUGUGACAUCACCAAAAGCCACUUGUGUCUAGGGAGUUAGUGAGGACUGCAGCUAGCAUCCAUGCUCUGAUGGGCAGAUGAACAAUGUCAAGGUGUGCAUCACUUUGCACCACAAUCAACUAUUGACACAUGCUUGCAGGUGAAAUUAGUUUCUGUACAACUGAUUUGCAGCUAUAGGCAAGGUAGAUGAAGUUGCUUUGCCAGUAAGGAAAAAUAGUAAUCUUUAAGAAAUUGACUCAUUGUUUAAUUUCUGGGGAUUUUCUUUAUACUUCUAAGCAGGCUCUUAUCUUUUAUUGGACAUAAUAUGAUUUUGAAAAAGCACAGUGCCUGACACAUUGCAAACACUCACCAACUGCUUGCUGAGGUGACAGAGUCACAAAAGUCUGCAUUCUUGUGCCUGAUGAUGCAUUUUGCGUACCUCAUACAGGCUCCUUGCCCACACUAUGGAAUGACAGCAGCCAGUGCAGGGAGGUUAAGUGACAUUUAAUGAGUGAAGCACUUAGCACUCUCUAGGUAAUAAGAUAGUGGUAAUUACUAGUGUUUUGGCAAAUGAAAAAUGCCCUGAAAUAGCCAAAUGUCUGAUUAAUGUUGGCAACUUAGAAGUCCUAUAAUCCAACUACCAGCCAAAGCAGGGAGCCUUUCUAUAAUUUGCCUUUUUUUUUUUUUUUUUCAAAAUCUGAGUCUUCUAAAAUCUUAUUAUUCCCAUUUUUACCAAUUGAGGCUCCUGUAGCAAAUAAGACCUCUUGAUAUUUUCAAGGACUGGUUAGAGGAUUUCUUUCAACCUUCACAUGAACAAAACAGCCUAUGGGUCAAAAUAAUGAAAUCCACCCCUGCCUGCUAGAUACUUGUCACCUUGCUAAAAUGCAAGGGCCUGGUCCAUUCAUUUUCCAAAUGCAGGAGUCUUGGUGCACUUCUCACUCUUCCUGCCUGUUCAUCUCUUUCAUGCCCACACAGACCUGUUUCCUUUUUGUCUCAUCAACGCCUCAUUCAUCCUCAUUACUGAGGCGUGUCCAAUGCUUUUUGACAUCUUUAUAGCAGUGCUGUUUCCUGGGCUCAGGAACCACACUGAGCUUGAGAUACUGCUGGAAGGAACCAUGUGGAGAGAAGGUUUGGGAGAACUUUGAGAGAGACUUAGUUUGGCCCAGCAUGUAAAACUUCAGUCCUGAACAUUUAUAGGGUUUUAUAGAAGGGCAUCCUCCAGGGCUGGUCCAUUCAGAGAAAUGCUGCAUGCUGCCGUCAUGGAAUGUGGCCCACAGGACACCAGAGCCGUGAGAACCGGAGAGCAGACUUCCCUCACGGCUGGGCUGAGCAAACCCUCCAAAGCCCUCCUCACGCAGUUACUAACAAUAGCAUGGGCUUACAGCACAAGCACGUGUUCUCACCUUUUUCCUAUGCCCUGGACUAAGGUUUGGCCAGUGUAAUCAUAUAAGGCCAUCCUGACAUUGUUUCUGUGUUUCAAAAUUUGGAUUUUUAUUUACAUUAGAACUACAUUGCUCCUAGUAGAACAUUACCUUUAGGGGACUAAUUUUCCAUGGAGAACUAUUUCAGCAUAUUGCAUGCUGCUCAGACCCCAAGUCAGAUAUGCCCACCAAGCCAGAUGAAGCUACACAAAUGUGGUAUUUAAAUGCAUUUUGUACAGUGACUUCAGAGUAUCUCACAUGACAUGGGUGUAAACUGGCUGGGGAGAAAAUGAUGCUUGUUCACCUCUUCCUCCAGCCGUGGUUAGGUGGUCCUAGGGGUAGCAGAGGGAAGGGAGGAUUUUGUGCAGUCAAGAUUUGCUUUUCCAUCCUUGUCUUCUGAAUGUCUAAAAUCUCUGCAUCUUUCUGAAGUUUAACAACUGUCUCCAGAGGUUUGCCAGGCAGCAGCUCUCAGAAGUUUCCAAAGCUUUGCAGAAUCUUAGAUCUGGAAUUAAAGAAUUCAAGCCCGAAUUGUGAGAACCAGAUAUUACUCAACAGAAAGCUCUUUCUAAGGAAUCUGAGCUGUUCACUGGUGGACAGUGGUGGGGCUUGAGUGCUCCUUGUUAAUAGGAUGGGCCAUGCACCCUCUCUGGAUAUUCACCAAGGCCUCUUCAGAAUAGGGUUUGUUCUGGCUAGAAGCGUGGUCUAGAAGAUGGCUAAGCUCUUUGCCAGCUCUCAUUUGGAGUUUUAUUAUUGCAUAAAAUCUUCGCUCACUCUGCAAAUCUUACGUAAUCUGGCACCUUCGGCACCAGGUGGUGCAGGGGCACUUCUAAGUGGGCUCUUUUUGUUACAGCACAACUCUCAGACAGUCCUGUGGGUCUUUGGAUUCGUCAGCAUUCCAGCAAACUAGCCCUGCUUAGAAGUUAGCACAAGACAGCAGAAUGCAGGACCCCGUAGGCAAAAUCACAACCUUGCUAUUAAAAAAAAUUUUGUUUUACAUACACAUUUGCAGGUGUUCCCUAGAGUGUGGUGUUUUGAAUUUGCUCUUUGUCAUCUGUAUAAUUGCCAAAUGAUUAUAGUGAUACACAUGACCUGCAUUCACUUUUUUCUAGUUUCCUUAAUUAUGUUUAGAAUAAAUUCAUUUCCCUAGACCGAGAACCACAAACAGGUAGUGUGGAGCAUACACCGAAUUUAGAAGCAUGUGGAUAAGGUCAGUGCUCACACUGCCUAGUCCACAGGGAGAGGAUGCUGCAUGAAUAUAUACUUGCCUCUGAGUGGAGGAGAAAUCGUGGCAUGAAAGAGAGAGUACCAGUGAUGACUUCUUAUCCCUGGAGCUGGGCUUUCACUGCUACCCAUAUCCCAGCCCUGCGAGUCUGUUCUAGCCAGCACAGACACCGCAGAUCCGGAACUGAAUGUUCCUAAAUGGCGCAGCCAAUCCAGGCUUUUCAGAAACUGGGCAAAAACAUUAAAAUGGGGACGAUCGGGUCUUCCGCAGUGGUCCAACACAGGAUUUCUUUUAAAUGUUUCAAAAACAUGUCCUUAAAAUUUCAGCCUGCUUCUUAGCGAGUGGGCCAGUUUUGCUUAAAACUGGUGGGGGGGCGGGGGGGAAGUUUUUAAAAAUUGCCAAAAAGUUAGAUGCAAAUGUAUUACUGUAUAAAGCAAAGCUGUAUAUACUAAACAUUUUUUAGCAGAGUAAUAUUUAUUUGCAUAGUCUAUUUAUUGUAUUCGUAUCACACUGUUAUUAAAUACUGGGAUGAAAUCAGUGACCUGAAGCAAGAAAUCUUGCCUUUUAAUGUAUCAUUAAUUAGGGCUGCUGUGAUAUUGUCAGCUUGCAUUAACAAUUAGAAGAUAGAGAACCCGCCAUCAGGGUGUCUACCUAACUUCUCAGGGACUACACUUGGUAGUUUUCCACCAUUUAAAGAACUGGUAAAUAUGAAACAUUUGUUGAGUUACCAGAAUUGCCAUUAACAGUGUUUUCUUUCCCAUAUUCCAUGCUUUCUGCCUCUGUGUAUAUAUAUAAUAUAUAUGUAUAUGACUGUGCUGUGUAUUUAUCGAAGCUAGUAAGCAAUAAUUUAUAUGUAAAAAUGGCCAAGCAAUAUAAGGUUAAAACUUAUAUAAGUAACCCUUACCUUAUCUUGUAUUUUCAAUUUUUUUUUAAAACUGCUUUUCCAAAUAUGAGACUAUGUUAAAGACACUAUUCAUGCCUCUUAGUUUCUUGCUUUCUCUGUGAUGUGUGUGGAUUAAAUAGCUCUGUUCUGGCAGCA